CCCUGUCGCCGCGGAGGGGCGGGGGCAGGACGCGCAACUCCGGCCGGAGCUGUCCGGGGUCGUGAGCCGGCCCCGCCUUGGUGGCGGCGCCCCCUCGCGGUCCAGAGGCAGACGCAUCGGGUGGGCUCGGGUCUCCAGCCCGGCCGGGAGGAGGGACCGGGUCUGCGGAGCGGGGACUCGGGGCCUCGGCGGGGCGCGCACACGCAGGCGGGGCGGCCCGGGGUGCGGGGCCUCUGCGCGGCUGACCAGGCUCCCAGAGCGUCAGCGCCGCCCAUGGCCGAGCCGCUCCAGCCAGACCCCGGGGCGGCCGAGGACGCGGCGGCCCAAGCUGUGGAGACGCCGGGCUGGAAGGCCCCGGAGGACGCCGGCCCCCAGCCCGGAAGUUAUGAGAUCCGACACUAUGGACCAGCCAAGUGGGUCAGCACGUCCGUGGAGUCUAUGGACUGGGAUUCAGCCAUCCAGACGGGCUUUACGAAACUGAACAGCUACAUUCAAGGCAAAAACGAGAAAGAGAUGAAAAUAAAGAUGACAGCUCCAGUGACAAGCUACGUGGAGCCUGGUUCAGGUCCUUUUAGUGAGUCUACCAUUACCAUUUCCCUGUAUAUUCCCUCUGAACAGCAAUUUGAUCCACCCAGGCCUUUAGAGUCAGAUGUCUUCAUUGAAGAUAGAGCCGAAAUGACUGUGUUUGUACGGUCUUUCGAUGGAUUUUCUAGUGCCCAAAAGAAUCAAGAACAACUUUUGACAUUAGCAAGCAUUUUAAGGGAAGAUGGAAAAGUUUUCGAUGAGAAGGUUUACUACACUGCAGGCUACAACAGUCCUGUCAAAUUGCUUAAUAGAAAUAAUGAAGUGUGGUUGAUUCAAAAAAAUGAACCCACCAAAGAAAACGAAUGAGAAAAAUGAAAGGAAGUUCUGCUGUCAGAGGCAAAACAUCUGUUUAUCAUAGACAUCAACAUGACCUAUAAGUAAAGUGCGUGUCUAGUGUCUUCUAUUGAGAGUACUACUAUUAAUUAAGCUUAUUUCCAAUGUGCCUUUUUAAUGCUUGAAGUUUUAUCUACAUACACAGGUAACAGAGGACAGUAGUCUGUAAACAUAUAAAUCGGUCAUAACUAUCGUGGUCUUUAUUUCUGUGAGGAUCUAGGGAAAUUUCAUGUCACUUCCCUCCUUCACUGCAUCACAAUCAUAUUCCCUUUUUUUUUUCUUGGAUUUGUGUCAGUUGGAUGAUAUCCCCUCCAGAUAGUAUCAAUAAAAUGUUAAAAUUAUUUAUCUUGUGUGGAACCCCUAGGCUGUCAGGCCCGGAGAGGUGAAAUUCAGCUGGACACAAAAAUCAAAUUGUCUUUUGUGGCUGCCACCAUUACAUUCUCUGUUGUAUGUAUUACUUUCCCUCCUGCAUCCUCCCACUGCCCCACUGCACAAGAAUACUCCAUGUAACUCCAUUUAAAUGUAAUGAAUUCAUUCCUUUCUUUCUGGUCUCCACUUAACCCCCUAAAAAUCUUGCUUUUUCCCCUAAACAUUUCCCUGAACUGUCACGUAUUUUCAUUCAUUCUUUAACUCAUUGUAGGGAGUCCCUGCUAUGUUCCAAGCACUCUGCUAAGGACUGGGAGGUGGUGGUAAGAAAACCUGUGUCCCAAGCCCCUCAUCACUGACUUCCUCUUCACUAACUCCAACAACAUCUUUCCACCUCCUUAACUAUUUCAUUCACCCUCCCACUGUGAACACCACAGACAAGGCCCCUGGCCUCAUGGAGUUUACAUUCUAGAGGGUGAGGGAGUUCAACACAAAUAAGAUGCUUGAAAUUGGCAAGUGUGAUGAAGAACAGAAUAGGGCAGUGGGGUAGAGUGUGGUUAGGUAGGGUGUGGUGGACAUCACAUAAGGUGGUCAGCAAAGGCCUCUCAAGAGACAGUUGAGACUUGAAUGACGAGGAUGAGUCAGAUGAAAGCCAGGGGCAGAGGUGAGGGGAGCAUCUUGGGCAGAGGUGACAGUGUUAAAGGGAGAGGCCACGUUCAGUACCCAGAACAAAAAGCUGCACACACUGCUUGCUGAGCAAGAGAGCACUGCUCUUGUAGGGCACGGUCUCUCGGAUAAAGAAAACUGCGGACCUUAUGCAGGGUUUUAGGAAGGAUUAACAGACUUUCAAAAGCAUUUAGGAGUCGAGGGAGCUUUAGUUGUGGGGAUGCAGUUACCAGAGUGAGGCCGCUGCUGAUUAGCAUGAUUUAGAAGCCUAGUUUGGAGGUGAGGUUACUGAUGGGAAAUUGUCAUUGAUUGUUUCUGGUACUUAAUUGCUACUGUGGCCAAAGGAUGGUCAGUUUUAUUCAGGAUUUGAAGUGGUGGCAGACAACGUGAGGUGUGCCACUCAAAUUCACCUUCAAGAAAGUACCAGCCGCCCAGCUGUGAGGGGUGUGGUUCGCCGACAGUCUCCCCGUUACCGUCUUCAGGGUCCACGCCAGAUUUCAAGAUAAGGACACACUAUUCUGUGGGAGAGAGGGACCUAGUCUACAACUGAGCAAGGCAGUGGUAGCUGACAGCAUGCUUUUUUCUGGCAAUUCCCAGCCAAUAACUGAGCAAGGUGGUGGUAUAAGACCUAGCCAUUUAGGCCAGGUGCAGUGGCUCACAGCUGUAAUUCCAGCACUUUGGGAGGCUAAGGUGGGAGGAUUGCUUGAGCCCAGAAGUUCAAGACGAGUCAUGGCAACCUAGUGAGACUGUCUGUCCAAAAAAUAAAAAAUUAGCCAAGCGUGGUGGCACACGCCUGUAUUCCUAGCUCCUGAGGUGAAAGGAUUGCUUGAGCUCGGGAGGCGGAGGUUGCAGUGAGUCCUGAUCAUGCCACUGCACUCCAGCCUGGGUGACAGAGCAAGAUCCUGUCUCAGAAAGAAAAAAAAAAGUCCUAGUCAUUUCUACCAACUCGAAAGCCCUCUAAUAAGCAGUCUCUGCUCUGGAGCUUUUUGGUGGGCUGCUAGAGACUUUGUUAGAUCCUACCGUUCCUCUGCUCAAUCCUGCUUUUCCCUUUUCCUUUCAGAGAUGUCACUUCACCAGUUUUGUACUCCUAACUCCAUCUCAGCCUAAAAUUGGCACAAUUGGUACCAGUGGCCCACGAACGUAGGUGGUAAGACAGCAUUUGCAGGCUGAGUGACUCACUGUCUGGCUGGCUCGGAGGCCCCCAUCCCUGGUGGAUAGGUGGCACAGACAGUCCCUGGCACAAGAAGGCUGUCCAGUGAUGAAGACUUCAGAUGAAAUGGCAUGCUGGUGCAGGGGAACGCAAUGACUGGUGGGUGAUUUGGGUGUCUCAAAUAUGGGAAGGGUGGAUAAAAGAGACAAGGACAGUGGGCUUCCAUGGUUAUUGCUGAGUUGGAUUGACGUCCUGCAAGUGGAUAAUGAAAAGCUGAGGUCAAUUAACAAACAAAACUAAGUGUGAGCCGCAGAGUCUCUGUGGUAGCUUGCCAACAAUCCUCAUCUCAUGCUGUAGCCAAGCAGAGCAAGCUGAAGGCCAAGCACAGGAUUUGAUGGUAAAAGUAGCUAACAGCCAACAAAUACUCAACCAAGCCAGGUCUGUUAGAUCAAGGUUGGAAUCAAACUUGGGAUCCCAAAACAUGGGAUGGGAGCAUUUAGUGGAUCUCCCCAACCAUCUGCCUCCCUAGAAAACUCCCUGAAUAUUCACAUCCUUCAGAAGAGGCCCACCCUUCCCCAUGAAGAGCUGGAACUACCCUCCCUUCCUGCCUCUUCCCUAACACAAGGGAAGACAGUGUCCAAGGUCUUUCCCCAUGAAGCAAAAGGUGUCCCUCAGGACUGGUCCCUCCCCUUCUCCUGGCUACCAGGCCUAUAACGAGACUUAAGUCACAACAUAACUGAUUGCGGCUGAGGGGUCUGAUGAGGGAGAAAUGGGAUCUAUGCCAGAGGAGCCACCUAACCUGGCAGCAUGUACUGCAGGGGCCAGGGGCGUACUCUUGGGACUGGAUCCUGAGGGUGCUUGGUCAAAGGGGCUGGGUUUAUACAACUAGAUAAAGGAGAGGGUAUAUUGACUUGGGGCUCUCAGGAUAGAGGAUUUCACACCAUGAGAAAAAUGCCAGGAGAUAAUACAGACUCACUGCUCUAGGGCAGCUUGGUAGAAGCCUAGAAAGAGUGAUCAAAAUGUUGAAAUGCCUGAAUGGCUGGGACAAACAAUAGAGAAAGGAAUGAGAAGGCUCAGGGAAGGGAGCAUGCCAGCAUGGAUAUAUGAGGCAAGGUGACCCAUCAGACAAUUAUGUUCCACGGGAAGGCCCAGGGGACCCAUCCUUCAGCAAGGCUGCUGGGAAUGCACUGAUAAGCGGGCUUGGGCAUCAUAAAGGAGCUCAGCGGUGGCUCUCCUCGGCAGGCUGGGGCUGGCAGGAAGGGCUGUGAUGGAACUUCACUUGCUGAGAGCAAUGUGGAUGAUGAUGAGACCUUGAAGAGCCCAGGUGGCAGUGCCAGCCACAGAAGCCAGGGUGCCAUCAGUAUCCUGUUAACCACUAAGCUCCAAAUGGCAGCCGAGGGGUCCUGACCUGUAAAGUCUCAUGGAAAUAGUUGGUAGAACAAGGCAUUCCUAGGGACAAAAGAGCUGACUAAUCAACAAGGGUAAGGCUUUAUAUAUAAUCAAAAGUGAGCAAGAAUUGAUGAGCAGGGGACUGAGAGAGAUCACUCCAAUUAAAAAACAAAAACAUGAUUCCUUGCCAGUUUCUAGUUCAGUUUUCUGACCUAGAGCUCAUUAAUUGCAGAGGUGACUGUAUCCUAGGGGAAAGUUUCCUGCAACAUUUCAGCAGGUGUACACAGUAAUGAUCCCCUCAUUCUUUUUCUAAAGGAUCUAUGGCCAUUUACUCAGGUGGCUCUACCCUGGGGAAAGAGGAAUACCUGGAUACGUCAGGGUCCAAGUUAACGUCUGAUACCCAGAAACCCAAAGAGUCAUUACAGUUCCUCCUCCUCCCAUUAAAAUGGGAGCAUACAGAGGUUAGAAAGUAAACGUAGUUCUAAUCAAAGUUUGGCUUACAGCAGAUCUCCUGGGCCUGCAGGUUAUCUGCCUAAUCCCUGAAUGUAUAAUUGAGACUGACAUCCUUGGCAGGCAGAAUAACCCCUACAUUUGUUCCUUGACCUGUGGGGAAAGAGUAUAAGCUUCUAAACUCCCUCUCCUCCAAUCAGGGCAGUAAACCAUAAUAAAUAUUGCCUUGAACAGUAUUUUUUAAGCACCUCGGGUGAACAUCUGCUUCUGGCCAUGAUGAUGAAUUGGGAACCCAAUUUACCUGUCCCUCUUAAACAACUAAAAGCCCAGACAAAAUAUAUGAAACAAUGGUUUUCAGACACUGAAAGUUCAUAGUACAGGACUGUGAUCUCUGCGAGAAGGGGGAAUAAUGAGGUGAGUCCAGUGAUUGCUCAGGCGAAUGGCCUGGAGGCAGUUUCUAGGCAGCAAAGCAGGGAGAGGGAAGCCAGAGACCAGUGGUCCUGCUGUGUUGAGGAGAUGGAGAUCAGUGUCACCGGAGGCCAAGGUGAGUAAGUGAGAGGAGAGGAGGCAGCAGCACACAGACAGAGAGUGCUGUAGAUCUGCAGUGGGUCCCCUGGAGUCCUUGGUUGAGUGAAGGUGUUAGAAGAAACUACUUAAGCCAAGAAAUGAGUAACUGGAAAUUAGUAGAGCAAAUAAUUUACAGAUCAUCUAUGGGGCUGGGAAAAGUUUGUGUUUCCACUAGCCAGAGUAGAAAUAACUCAUAAUGCAUGGGUCAUCAGGUGGAGUCCUCCAACAGGUGUUGCCUUAGUACUGAGGUCAAAUUGUCCCUAGACCAAAGGCUUCUUUGGACUUCCCCUAACAAAGCUUAAAGACAAGCCUUGGAAGGAUCAAACUAAUUUCAAGAAACUUAACUGUGAAUCAGAAUAAAACCCAAUACCAUUUAUAGGAAUAUAACAAAAUCCAUCAACAAACAACAUAACACUCAUAAUUACCAACAUUCAGUAAAAAAUUACUGGAAACAGAGAAAUAUAAAUUAUGGCCCAUAAUUAGGAAAAAAGGGUAAUCAUUAGAAGUAGAACCAGAAGUGACAGAUAUGAAGAAAUUAGCAGCUUGAAUUAUGUGAUGUGGCAGAUCUUAUGUAUUGGAGGUAGGGGGAAAGAAGAUGCAGUGUGGAAUAGAUGACAAGGCCCAAUGAGAGAAUCACAGUGCAGGUCCCUGGGGCCCUGAAGGAAGGUGGUUCUAACCACAGGAGAGGAUCAUAUGCUUUUUGAAAAACAGCCUCUGCUGUGCUACUGGGCCCUGGUAGACACGGAACUUUGAGACCCAGUGAUGCUGUAUCCAGAACUGCUCAUCUUAACUAGGUCCUGUGGGAAGCACUAAGUCAUAAGCUAGUAGGAUCGGCAGCAGCCCAUUGGAAGAUGGAAAUGAUAUGUACAGGAGCAGUUCCAAGCCAGACCAGAGGACAUAAGCAAACUGCAAGAGCAAUUACUCCAACCGCCAUGUCUGCACAGUGGCACCUACAUCCCCCCUCCCUGUGGUUGUUGGAGGACCUGUAUGAUCCACUGAAGGAAGAGGAAUGCUUGGGCUUGGUUUAUUGAUUAGUUAUCUUCUGUAGUUGCAAGCUGAAAAUGGACCUUCACUCAAAGGUGACAUUGAAAAACGGGAAAAAAAUUGCAAUCUUCCUGCAAAAACUGGGCAGAAUUUUUUGAGGUACACUGGAUCAUUCACCUUGUGAGGGAGGACAGGUAAAAUAUUUAUGGAAGUGGCAGAAAAUGGCCUGCCAGCUGAUCAGGAGUUUGGGAGGAAAAAAACAUGGAUUAGGAGGUCUGGGGUAGAGGCAUGUGGAUGGGCAUAUGGAGUGAACACAGAAGUUGAAAAACUGUAUCACAUGUUAAUGCCCACUAGAUAGCACCCACCAGAGAAGAGGCACUAAACAACCAAGUAGAUGAAAUGACUUAGCCUGUUCUAUUAGCUUUUGCCAGUGCCCACCUCAGUGCUGGUAAAAUGCACACAUAAAGUGGCAGUGGUGGCAAAGAUGGAGGCUAUGGAUGGAACCCACCAACAUGGGCUCCCACUUACCAAGGCCAACUUAGACACUGCUCACUGUGACUAUCCAACCUGCCUGCAACAAAUACCAAUGCUGAGACCCUGAUGAGGCUGUGAAGACCAACUGGUCGCUUGAUAGCAAAUUCACUAUGGUAGGCUCAUUCUUUCCUAGAAGCACCAGCAGUUUAUUCACACAAGGACAGACUUCCUAUUCUAGGUAUGUGGUUCCUUUCGGGCCUACAGGGUCCUGAACACAAUCUAAGGACUUACAAAACAUCUGAACUGUCAGCGUAGAUUUGCUGAAUACGUGAUCUAUACAUGUUAACACCCAAUCAGGGAGAGUUCGCCAGCGGUCAUAGGAUCCACUGCUCCUAUCACAUACUGCGCCACCUAGAAGCUGCUAGACUGAUGGAAUGUUGGCAUGGCCUGCUUUAGUGCCAGGUGGGAGACAAUACCCUGCCAAGAUGUGCCACCGUCUCCUGCACACAGUAUACUUAUUGAAUCAGAAAGCCUGUAUGAUGCUGUGUCUACAACAGGAAUAUAUAGAUUUCAGAACCAAGGAGUGGAGGCAGGAGUGACCCCACUUACCAUCGCACCCAACGAACCACUGAGGGACUUAGUACUUCCCAUGCCCACAACUCCAGGUUCUACAGCAUCAGAAGUCCUAGUUCUCAGAGACUGUAUACCUUCUCUAGGCAAUAUUGCAAGAAUCCCAUUGAACUACAGUCUGCUGCUACUAUGUGGGCACUUUGGACUCUGUGUUCAGGGACCAGUAGGCAAGAAGUCACCAUCUAGUCAAGGGUAAUUGACCCUGAACUGCAGGAGGAGGCAAGCCUGCUGUCAGAGGAUAGUGGCGAGAGCAAUGUGUGUGGAACUUAGCGGACCCACUGGAGGCACCCUCUGUACUCCUUGCCCAGUUGUAACUGAAUGGACUAGUGCAGCAACCCUGGUCUGAGAAGGGUUUGGCUCCCAGGAGCUCAGGACCCUCAGGAAUGAGAGCUUGGUUUAUACUAUCAAAAAAGCCACCAAGACCAGCAAAGAUGACAGUUGUGGGUGAGGGGAAUUUAGAAUGAAGCAGGGAGUAAUGAGGACCAGUUGUGGUUCCAAAACCAUUUGCAGGAAGGUGCUAUAGUUGGUCCUACCAAACUCCUCUUUCAACAUUUAUCCUCAGGAAGAGAGGUCCAUUGGCGCCCUGAAACAGUCACUCUCUGCGUGUUUUUGGGAAAAUGGAUCCACAUAGGCAAGGGGUGGACCAUGGCAGGCAUAGAGCGGUGCCACUUAGAUCCCCCUUCAAGACAAGAUAUGCCAUCCAGCUGCAAGGAGUGUGGGUAGCUGGCAGCCACCAGCUGCUACUUCACCAGGAUCCACCUUAGCUUUCAAGCUGAGGUCACGCUAUUCUCAAGACAGGAGGGGUUGGUGGCCAAUGAUUUCACUAAAUUAUGGAAAUUGAGAGCAUGCUUUUCUGAGGGGGCCCUCUUGCCAAAGACCAAGCAAGGCCAUGGUACAAGGACCUAACUGUUUCAGUCCAACACAGGACUCCUCCAAUGAGUGACCUUUUUCCCAGAGUUCCCCUGGGAUGGCAGCUCGCCUGCUCUCCCUGCCUCGUCCUGCUUCCUCUUUUCCUUUCAAAGGUGCUUACUCCAAUAAUAAAUCCUUUGGUAUUCUAACUGUCUACUUCUUGAAGAAUCUAAACUGGCAGUAGGAUCAUGCCCCUCACUGAUAGCUCAACCACGUUUUCUAUCUUUGGGCCUCCUUGUCUUUACCUAGCACAUGAGAAGCAUUUAUUAGGACUUUUUUUCCCCCAUUGCUGAACAAAUGACUACAGAUUGCUCUACCUCUUGUUCUGUGAAUAAAGGCUGGCCGCUGUGGAAGGUAGGUCAGAGCAGGCAACUGAGAGAAACUGUAUUACAGUUACCGAGUGGCUUAUUAAGGAAAGUGGCGCAACAAUCAGGUCCAUGUUUCAUUCAAAUGACCCUCCAUUCCCCCAACAACAUCCUCACAUCUGCCAAAGCAAAUUAUGCUGCUGUGCUCAUUUGAUGAUGGAAUCAGCAUCGCAUGCAGGCUGAACCCCUACUACGGCAGAACCAAGAAAGCCACUCUUUCCCCUCUCCUCCUAAGAUGCCACCACAGAGCAGGGUGCCAGUGGUGGGUGGGGAGAAAGACGGAGACACAGAAACGUCUCCUUUUCACUGUGAUUCUCCUAAGGAAUAUACAGUCACCCCCACAGGAAAAGCAAGAGUUCAAUCAAGAUUCUUCAGAAAUAGUAGGAUGGCAGAAAGCAGAUCGCAUUGAGGUUGUUUCCAACUGACAGACCAAGCAGUAAUUUGUUUCUCUCCCCACUGAUAGUAAAAAUAAAGUGGAAAUAAUUUAGGGCUGGGGCUUCUGUGAUUAUCUGGAACUUAAAGUAUGAGGGUAUGAGAGCCAUCAGAUCUACCCCUGUGGAGCUUUUUAAGAUGCGGUCCAUAACAGAAGCGGGCCCCAAGGAGUAGAGUAGCCACAUGGAAGGUGCCAUGUUUCAGGGAUGAGUCUCGAUUCUUCUCUCCCUGUAUUUCAUCCAUGCCUGUAAGAAGUUCUCACGUCUCUCCACAUGCCACGUCAUCUGAACCGCCAGGCGAUAGGUUAUUCGUAUUUUAUUCCAAAGUCCAUAGGACACGAUGUGGACUUGUUUUUCCACGUGCCCUUGUAGAUGGUGCCAUCCAGUGUCUGUGAUGUUCCACCUCCUCUGUUGGGUUGUCACCUCCCCCAGAGACCUUCUGGUCUCACUGCUUUUCUGUUUGUAUCCAGCAAAACACUCAACAAUUCUGUAUAAGAACACCUAUCUCAUUAUUCAAAAAAAAUGCAUGUAUAAACAAAAAGAAAUAUUUCAAAUAUUUACUUUACAAUUGUUUUAUUCAAAGGAAAUUAAAUACAAAUGUAUAUUUUUCAUUAAAAAUGGGGAUUUAAAAAUAGUUUUAUAAUUAGUGUUAUGUUGCUUUAUCUUAUCUUUGCAUAAAUUAUGUAUUAUUAAAGGUUUCUGAUAUCCAUA